AGUCUCCUCCUCUGCGUCCUCGGCCGCGGCCCGGGUCCCUCGCAAAGCCGCUGCCAUCCCGGAGGGCCCAGCCAGCGGGCUCCCGGAGGCUGGCCGGGCAGGCGUGGUGCGCGGUAGGAGCUGGGCGCGCACGGCUACCGCGCGUGGAGGAGACACUGCCCUGCCGCGAUGGGGGCCCGGGGCGCUCCUUCACGCCGUAGGCAAGCGGGGCGGCGGCUGCGGUACCUGCCCACCGGGAGCUUUCCCUUCCUUCUCCUGCUGCUGCUGCUCUGCAUCCAGCUCGGGGGAGGACAGAAGAAAAAGGAGAAUCUUUUAGCUGAAAAAGUAGAGCAGCUGAUGGAAUGGAGUUCCAGACGCUCAAUCUUCCGAAUGAAUGGUGAUAAAUUCCGAAAAUUUAUAAAGGCACCACCUCGAAACUAUUCCAUGAUUGUUAUGUUCACUGCUCUUCAGCCUCAGCGGCAGUGUUCUGUGUGCAGGCAAGCUAAUGAAGAAUAUCAAAUACUGGCGAACUCCUGGCGCUAUUCAUCUGCUUUUUGUAACAAGCUCUUCUUCAGUAUGGUGGACUAUGAUGAGGGGACAGACGUUUUUCAGCAGCUCAACAUGAACUCUGCUCCUACAUUCAUGCAUUUUCCUCCAAAAGGCAGACCUAAGAGAGCUGAUACUUUUGACCUCCAAAGAAUUGGAUUUGCAGCUGAGCAACUAGCAAAGUGGAUUGCUGACAGAACGGAUGUUCAUAUUCGGGUUUUCAGACCACCCAACUACUCUGGUACCAUUGCUUUGGCCCUGUUAGUGUCGCUUGUUGGAGGUUUGCUUUAUUUGAGAAGGAACAACUUGGAGUUCAUCUAUAACAAGACUGGUUGGGCCAUGGUGUCUCUGUGUAUAGUCUUUGCUAUGACUUCUGGCCAGAUGUGGAACCAUAUCCGUGGACCUCCAUAUGCUCAUAAGAACCCACACAAUGGACAAGUGAGCUACAUUCAUGGGAGCAGCCAGGCUCAGUUUGUGGCAGAAUCACACAUUAUUCUGGUACUGAAUGCCGCUAUCACCAUGGGGAUGGUUCUUCUAAAUGAAGCAGCAACUUCGAAAGGCGAUGUUGGAAAAAGACGGAUAAUUUGCCUAGUGGGAUUGGGCCUGGUGGUCUUCUUCUUCAGUUUUCUACUUUCAAUAUUUCGUUCCAAGUACCACGGCUAUCCUUAUAGUGAUCUGGACUUUGAGUGAGAAGAUGUGAUUUGGACCAUGGCACUUAAAAACUCUAUAACCUCAGCUAAUAACAAAGAGGAAGGCAAAGUUAAUACAUGUUCCUUCUAGAAGAUACAGGUAAGCAAAAUGAAGAAAAUAUAUUCAUAAAUCCCAACACCCAGGUCAUCAAAUGUCAUCAGUUUAGCCUGUACAUAUUUUGAACCUUGGGAAUUAUGUAAUACAUAUUUUGUAAGCUGCUUAUUUUUCUUUUAUACAUCAUGAGCAUAUUCCUAUGCAGUUAACUACAUUCUACAAUAUAUAUGAUUUUACACCUAUGUAGUAAUAUCAAUGUAUGAAUUGCCACAACUAUUUUAAGUUUUAUGCCAUCCAGCUUUUUAUGGUGUAUCUUUCAGUACACCCUGUGGUUUAAUACAAGACUAAGUAACUGCUGUCUGUGUUAGUUUAUCCUACAAACUAAGAAUGGCUUCUACAGUUCUAAAUCAUUGGGGGGUGGGACGUCAACAAAGAAUAUUUUGUGACAUGAAAAUUAUGAAAUUCAGAUAUCAGUGCCUAUGAAUAAAGUUUCAUUGAAACGCAGCCAGGUUUGUUUUAUGUGUUGGCUGCUUUUGCACUACGACAGUUCAGCUGAGUGGUUUCAGCAAAGACCCAUGGCCCACAAAGUUUAAAAUACUUAACCUUCUGGCUCUUUACAGAAAAUGUGCUAACUCCCGGUUUAGCCAUGCUGAACACAGCACUGAAUAUGUUCCCAUACUUUCAUACCUUUCCUCAUCCAGUUUCUUCGGUCGAGGCUGCUGUCCCUGCAUCUUACUUGUUCUCAGAGUUUUGCUUUUUCAGUUCUUGUAACACCGUCAUCAUCUCAAAUAUGUCACUGUAUCAUACUUAAUCACACCCAGGUCUUUCCUUUAGCUAAAAGAAAUGUAAGGGCCAUGACUUUCAGUCAUUUCAUUUUCUGCAACAUGCUUCUAUGCACAGAAUCUAGUACACAAUGGUUGUUAAAUGCUGAUUGAAACAGACUUUUGGGGGCCCUGAGAUUAAGAAAAUAGCUAACACUUGCGUGUUUCUCUAGAAAAAUCUUUUGAAUUUCAAGUAAUAAACUUGCUAAUAAACCUAUGGAAUAUUAAUCCUUAGCAAAUCAAAGACAGCAUUUUCAUCUAAAUUGUGGUUUUCUACCAUGAGGGAGUGCUGAGGAGAGAGCCAGCCUUAAGGAGAGAAACGGUUUGAAGUUUCUUCUUUGUGUAAACAGUCUCUCUGCAUCCCUGAUGGACUUUAAGCAAAAAUAAAGUGACACAGACUAGAAAGGAAUGGUUGCUUCUCUUAGGCUAGGGGAAGUGGGAGCUUCUGGGGGCACAUUUGUGCUAGUCCUAGCCUUCUAUCUAUCUUAUCCCUUGUGUGCGAUUUGCUACUCUUGCCAAUUAGCUUCCAUUUUCUAUUACUAUCUCAGUUACAGUUGACCAUGCAUAUAUUCUCUUCAGAAUACGCGAAUAAGCCAGUCACAGCAAUCAGUGCUAUGCACAUGCAGACUACUACUAUGGAUAACUACAGUGCGAUUCGUUCAUGACUGAGCGUGGAGCAGAGUCCACACAGAAGUUGAUCGUGGUACCCAAGGCUGCUUCUCACUCAUUCUGGAAGCAGACCGCAAAAGUGAAAAGCACACAUCAGGGGAAUACAUUCAGUUUUCAUUAUUGACAGUUGUUUUUAAAAAAGUAUGAUACGAAGGCAUUUAUACAUUUUUGUGAUAGGCAUUAUUAGAAAAAACAAUAUCCAGGCACUCCUGAACCAUAAGUUUGUGAGAACUAUUAUACUGUUAGAUUAAGAAGCAAAAGUAUUUAUUAGACAGAUAAAUGUGAAAAGGGAAAAAAAUACGUGUCAGAUCUUGUUUAGAAAUGAGAGACUAAUUCCUUGAGUGAUAAUAUCAAUAUAAAACAUUCAUACUGGAACAUACUUUGGAAAUUUAAUAUUUAUAAUUUAAUAUUUAUAUAAUGAAAAUAAAAGUGAAACCUGAAAUACUGAUUAGAGAACAGCAGUUCAUACUUUUCUCAGAAACGUUUUAACCAGUCAAAACAUUUUUGACAUUUUUGUGCUUCAAGUGUUUCCAGUGUCUUGAACAAAUAAAGAAAUUUUUAUAACUAUUUAAAAUGAAAAUGAUAGUUUUGAAAAUGAUAGAAGCAUAGGAAGUACUCUAAUUGUCCUACAAUAAAGGAUACAUCUAACUAACAAGUAAUCAGUUUCAGAUUAAAUAUAUAUUUAUCAUUUCAUAAUGAUAUAAACAACUGAUUGUUACACCAGGUUAAGAAAAUUACUAAAUGAAAAAAACAGUAGCAUAACUAAAGAUAACAUUAAUAAAGUACUCACAGAGAUCCUUUUACUGUGAAUAUACCUAAGUAUCAUAAAACUGCUAAAAAGUUAGAAGGUAUAAAAUUACCAGUAUGGAUCAGAUUAGUAUUUUUGCUUUUACAGGGGUAAUAUCGUUAGCAGCAAUAAAGAUUACCUUUAGUGCUCCGUAACUUGAAAUCUGCAGAGCCUUUAAACACUAAACAACAAAAAGCUACAAAUCCCUAGUUUUAAGUAUCAGUUCAUUUUAUGAUUAAGGUUUCUUUUUUCAUUAACCCUCAUUCUUCAGUUAGCUUCAUCUUCAGAGCAAGCUGAUGAUGGCUUGUGUGUGCUAGCAGGAUGAACGCUAUCUUUUCAAAACAUAAUGCCACAGUUCAUGUACAGCUGGCACAUCUAUCUGCUUUACCAGCAGUGUUUUUAAGGAUCAUGCGGAUUGAACAGCAACUACAGCUUAAGGCCCUGACAAGGUUUACUGCUGACAUUCUUCAUGGAGAUGGUCACCCUUAUCGUACGCUUUAUUCGUUACUUAUUAUCUUGAAAGUAGAGGCGACGUCUCAUUGCAUCCUGAUAUCACCACAUCAUUUUUAUCUUCUAAUUUAACAAUUUCUCAGAAACAGCUAACAAGAGUAAUUUUUCUAGUUUGUAUUGUACUGUGACUUUAUUUACAUUUUAAUUGAUGUUAUAUAAUAUACACUGUAUAUUAUAUAAUUUAAAUAUAUAUUUCAUGUUUUAUACUAAAAUGUUACAUUUUAAAAUACAUAUUUAUUCUUGCACAUAGUAUCACCAGAAUCCUAAAAUAUUAGCACGAAAAGAACUUCGGGAAUCAUCCAAAACAAACGUUCUUUUCACUAAUGAGGAAACCGAGGUUCAGAAAGACGAAACAAUUUAUGCCUAGGAUGAUAUGAUUUAAACAUCCAAAUAUAAAACUUACCUACUUUGGACAUUUUUCCAGCUACAUGUUUUUUUUUUGAUGUUGUUGUUUUUUGUUUUCUUUUUUUAAGUACAAGAACUAUUAAUUUCAUUUUUGCUUUUAUAUUUAAUUAAAAAUUGGUUUGUCUCUGGUUGCCUUGCAAAGUUGUCUUGUGUUGUCAAGACUCAAAAAGAACAUGCCACGUGUUAGCAGAAAGGUACAGAUGUAAACAAAAGCUUCAUAAAUGUUAUUUAAAUUGAUUUACCAUCUUACAAAAUUAAAUUUUGUUUCAUAAAUUAAAGCUUUGCUUAGGGAAGUUUAAAAAAAUAACAUAGUUAUCUUUUACUUUUAUAUGUACAAGUAUCUCUGCUGAUGUUUCAUCAGAAAUUUUAUGAUUCAUGAUUUGUGUAUACUCUUUUUGGUUGUUCAAUAUGAUGAAAUUGUAAAUUAACAAAAGACCAAGUGAUUAAAUUAUACGGUUAGAGAAAAAAUAUUUUUAGGACAUUCAAAUGACCCACUUCACGCAUUUGUUUCAGUCCAUUCCCUUGUAUUUCCCCUACAUUACCAUUUUAAAUGCUGAUUUAACUGCUGUUCUAGCCAGCAAUGAAAGGAAUGUCUAUGUAAAUUUAAACCACAAAUUAAAGCUUUCAGCAUCUUCUCUCACCCUGACCCUGUUCCCAACCUAAGCCUCAUCUGGUUAAAGGCACUAGUUUAGAAAAAUUGCCCUGAUGUAAAAAUUACAAUUAGUUGAAUACAAUUAUGACAUUUUAAUGUUAUAUUUACAUGUGCUAAUUUAGAAUGGAAUAACAAACAUAUUGUAUUUUCCUUAUGUUCUAUGUUCAGCACAUAAUAAUUUUCUUUCUUUUUCAGCUUUUUAAUUAAAUGAAGCCAAGUGGGAUUUGCAUAAAGUGAAUGUUUACCAUGAAGAUAAACUGUUCCUGACUUUAUACUAUUUUGAAUUCAUUCAUUUCAUUGUGAUCAGCUAGCUUAUUCUUGUGUACUUUUUUUAAACUGUGGGUUUUCCUAGUAAAUUUAAUUUACAGAAAUCAAUGGUAGCAUUUAGUAAUCUACAAAGGAAAUAUCAAAGUGUUUUUCAAGCCUGUUAUAUUCAGUGUGUGCCACAGGAUUGAAAUAAAUGACAAUGUAAUUAUGAA